GGCUCAUCCCUCUGCAGAGCGCGGGGUCACCGGAAGGAGACGCCAUGACGCCCGCCCUCACAGCCCUGCUCUGCCUUGGGCUGAGUCUGGGCCCCAGGACCCGCGUGCAGGCAGGGCCCUUCCCCAAACCCACCCUCUGGGCUGAGCCAGGCUCUGUGAUCAGCUGGGGGAGCCCCGUGACCAUCUGGUGUCAGGGGAGCCUGGAGGCCCAGGAGUACCAACUGGAUAAAGAGGGAAGCCCAGAGCCCUUGGACAGAAAUAACCCACUGGAACCCAAGAACAAGGCCAGAUUCUCCAUCCCAUCCAUGACACAGCACCAUGCAGGGAGAUACCGCUGCCACUAUUACAGCUCUGCAGGCUGGUCAGAGCCCAGCGACCCCCUGGAGCUGGUGAUGACAGGAUUCUACAACAAACCCACCCUCUCAGCCCUGCCCAGCCCUGUGGUGGCCUCAGGGGGGAAUAUGACCCUCCGAUGUGGCUCACAGAAGGGAUAUCACCAUUUUGUUCUGAUGAAGGAAGGAGAACACCAGCUCCCCCGGACCCUGGACUCACAGCAGCUCCACAGUGGGGGGUUCCAGGCCCUGUUCCCUGUGGGCCCCGUGACCCCCAGCCACAGGUGGAGGUUCACAUGCUAUUACUAUUAUACAAACACCCCCCGGGUGUGGUCCCACCCCAGUGACCCCCUGGAGAUUCUGCCCUCAGGCGUGUCUAGGAAGCCCUCCCUCCUGACCCUGCAGGGCCCUGUCCUGGCCCCUGGGCAGAGCCUGACCCUCCAGUGUGGCUCUGAUGUCGGCUACGACAGAUUUGUUCUGUAUAAGGAGGGGGAACGUGACUUCCUCCAGCGCCCUGGCCAGCAGCCCCAGGCUGGGCUCUCCCAGGCCAACUUCACCCUGGGCCCUGUGAGCCCCUCCCACGGGGGCCAGUACAGGUGCUAUGGUGCACACAACCUCUCCUCCGAGUGGUCGGCCCCCAGCGACCCCCUGAACAUCCUGAUGGCAGGACAGAUCUAUGACACCGUCUCCCUGUCAGCACAGCCGGGCCCCACAGUGGCCUCAGGAGAGAACGUGACCCUGCUGUGUCAGUCACGGGGUUAUUUUGACACUUUCCUUCUGACCAAAGAAGGGGCAGCCCAUCCCCCACUGCGUCUGAGAUCAAUGUACGGAGCUCAUAAGUACCAGGCUGAAUUCCCCAUGAGUCCUGUGACCUCAGCCCACGCGGGGACCUACAGGUGCUACGGCUCAUACAGCUCCAACCCCCACCUGCUGUCUUUCCCCAGUGAGCCCCUGGAACUCAUGGUCUCAGGACACUCUGGAGGCUCCAGCCUCCCACCCACAGGGCCGCCCUCCACACCUGCCUCACACGCCAAGGAUUACACAGUGGAGAAUCUCAUCCGCAUGGGCAUGGCAGGCUUGGUCCUGGUGUUCCUCGGGAUUCUGUUAUUUGAGGCUCAGCACAGCCAGAGAAACCCCCAAGAUGCAGCCGGGAGGUGAACAGCGGAGAGGACAAUGCACCCU